CCAGGCCCUGGGCGAGCUAAGGUUUCUGUGAAUAGAGUCCCGCUGCCACACUGGUGCAUCUUGAACCUCUAGGGCAGUUGGCAAACUACAGCCCGUGGGCCAAAUGCAGCCUACGACCUGUUUUUGUACAGCCUUUGUGUUAGGAAUGGAUUUUACAUUUUCCAAGGGUUGUAAAAACACAGAGACCAUCUGGCUGGCAAAGCCUGAAAUAUUUGCCAUCUGGCCCUUCACAAAAGAAGUUUGCUGCCCCCUGAUCAAGAGGAUUCCAAGAGAUAAUGUGUGGAAAGUGCUGAGUGUAGGGGCUGGCACACAGUCGAUGCUCAAUAAAAGGCAGCUAGUGGCAGUUAGGUGCAAUCAUAGCAAAUGGAUAAAAUGCUUAGAGACACAGAAAGUAUUGAAGAAAAGCAAAACAGUGACAAAACAAUAAACAACAGUAUAUUAAAAGUACCAGUGGUUGAAAAAUACUUGUCUAGGAUUAUUUAUUUCAUUGGGCAAAUCGUUCUUGGGCAAAGCAUGUACAGCAGGGGUCAGCAAAUUUUCUGUCAAGGGCCAGGUAGUAAAUAUUUUAGAUUUUGUAGGUCAACUGAUCUGUCAAAACAAUUCAACUUUGCCAUCGUAACACAAAACCAGCCACAGCCAAUAUGUAAAUGAAUCAAUGCAACUCUGUGCCAAUAAAACUUUAUUUACAAAAACAGAGUUUGGCUGCCAGUUUGCCAACCCCUGAUCUAGAACGCCCAGGGAACAGCUGUGUGAUCUCAGCCAAGUGCUUUCUGCCCUGACUGGUUUCCACAUCUGCAGCAAAAGUGUAACAGAACUGCCUGCAUGGGACAUUGUGAGGAUUCAAUGCAGAAAGUGCCUUGAAUGCGGAGGUGUUUAACAAAUGGUGAAAUAAGGACGCCUCUCCUCUUCUUUCCCCACUGUGGCUGCUGGGUACUUUCUGUGGGCCUGUUACUGUGCCAGGCAUUUGGAGCAAUGAAUGAUAUAAGUUGUGGUCCCAGUUCUUAGAAAGCUGAUGAUCUGGUCAGAGAGAGAAGGACAAGACAAACAGAUCUAGGGACAGUGGCAGCCAGAACUCAGAAGAGAGCUGAAGGACCCAGAGGGCUUCCUGGAAGAGGUGGCCCUAGGGCAAGACCAUCCUGCAGGUCAACUUUGCUUGAUUGGAGGUGGCUGCCUAAAAUCAGGCUAGAGCAGUAAGAAUCUGUGAUAGAUUAGCAAUGUCUGUCACAAGCCCAGCACAAGAUGGGGGAAGUAUGUCUGCCAUUCUCAUCCUGUGUGGAGCAGCAGGGCUUGGCAAAGGGGAGAGGAGGCACAAAGGUGCCUUGGCUGGGGUGGCCGACCUGCAUGUGGGAGCCACUCCAAGUCCCCUUCUCCAUGGCCCAGCAGGCAUGGCCCCCCGAGGCAUGCCAGGUCUGGGCCCCAUAACUGGCCACAGAGACAGCCAGAUGAGCCAGUUCCCCGUGGGGGGCCAGCCCUCAUCUGGCCUGCAGGACCCGCCGCAUCUGUACUCACCUGCCACCCAACCACAGUUCCCGCUCCCCCCGGGUGCCCAGCAGUGCCCUCCUGUGGGCCUCUAUGGCCCCCCAUUUGGGGUGCGGCCCCCCUACCCCCAGCCCCACGUGGCUGUGCAUUCAUCUCAAGAACUGCACCCCAAACACUACCCCAAGCCCAUCUACUCGUACAGCUGUCUGAUCGCCAUGGCCCUGAAGAACAGCAAGACAGGCAGCCUGCCUGUGAGCGAGAUCUACAGCUUCAUGAAGGAGCACUUCCCCUACUUCAAGACGGCCCCCGACGGGUGGAAGAACUCGGUGCGGCACAACCUGUCUCUGAACAAGUGCUUCGAGAAGGUGGAGAACAAGAUGAGCGGCUCCUCCCGCAAGGGCUGCCUGUGGGCUCUGAACCUGGCCCGCAUCGACAAGAUGGAGGAGGAGAUGCACAAGUGGAAGAGGAAGGACCUGGCUGCCAUCCACCGGAGUAUGGCCAACCCUGAGGAGUUGGACAAGCUGAUCUCCGACCGGCCUGAAAGCUGCCGGCGCCCCGGCAAACCGGGGGAACCAGAGGCCCCCGUGCUGACUCACGCCACCACAGUGGCCGUGGCGCAUGGCUGCCUGGCUGUCUCCCAGCUCCCACCCCAGCCACUGAUGACCCUGUCCCUGCAGUCAGUCCCCCUGCACCACCAGGUCCAGCCCCAGGCACAUCUUGCUCCAGACUCUCCAGCACCAGCCCAGACCCCGCCACUGCACGCCCUGCCGGACCUCAGCCCCAGCCCGCUCCCCCACCCCGCCAUGGGAAGGGCUCCUGUAGACUUCAUCAACAUCAGCACCGACAUGAACACUGAGGUGGAUGCCCUCGACCCGAGCAUCAUGGACUUCGCUCUGCAGGGGAACCUGUGGGAGGAGAUGAAGGAUGAGGGAUUCAGCUUGGACACACUGGGCGCCUUUGCAGACUCCCCGCUUGGCUGUGACCUGGGGGCCUCAGGCCUAACCCCUGCCUCGGGUGGCAGCGACCAGUCCUUCCCAGACUUGCAGGUGACGGGUCUCUACACAGCGUACUCCACUCCGGACAGUGUGGCUGCAUCGGGCACCAGCUCCUCCUCCCAGUACCUGGGUGCACAGGGGAACAAGCCUAUAGCCCUGCUUUGAGCUGUCAGCCUCACCUGCCCUGGAACCCCGGCACCCGGCUUGGGCAGAGAACUGACUAGAACAGGGUGUUCCCAGAAGGCAGGUCCCUCAUUGUCCCCGAAGCCUCUCCUGGACCUGUGGCGAAGUUGCCGGCUGGACAGGGAAGCGGUUCCCCUCAGCAGCCCCUCUCCUUCUCGUGCCUCCCCCUGGAGCUUCCGGAGCAGUUUCUGGGGGCUCUUCCAAGUCAGAAGAAUGGAGGAAGGUGGACAAGCAACCCAGCAUCCCCCGACCCCUUGACACUCCUCCGAGGCCUGAGCCGCAAUGCCUGCCCGUGUUGAGUGAGACUUCUCCAUCCUGGAUCCUGGCUGCGUGACCUCAGUGACCUGCACCCCAUUUUGGGACACCUUGGUGCAUUAAGGAAACACCCUGGGGUGAAAGCCCUUGAAUUCAUCCUCAUGGGAAAUGGCUGAGUGGAUCAAACCUCAGCCGCAGCCUCCGGGGGACAGGCCCAGGGCGGGAAAUGGAGCCGGAGAAGCUUGAGCCUCUCUCUUGGACAGGACAAGCUGAACUCUGAAAUGGGAGCCGGUCCAGGUGGCCUUCAGCCCCACCUUUCCGAUAGUCUGUUAGAAUUUUAUUAGCGCAGAUUCCUGGGCCAUGCCGGGUACCGUGACCUUGUGUAAAUUUAUUUAUAUUUAUUGUGGCCCAUCCACCCCACUUCUGCAAACCCAUCCCGAGGCCUCUGGAAUGGGACUCCUUCUCCCUCCCUACCUCCCAGCCAUCCUAACUCCUACAGGCCAGAGAAUGACAUCUCUAACUGGCUCAUAAUCCCUUGGCAGCCUGGGGCUACUUUUUAGAACCAGCAAGCACUGUUGAUACUGUGAAACAUCCCAUUUUUUCCGUAUUAGAGACCAGAUAUUUUUCUACCUGUUCAUGAUUCACAUCUCUUCUUGCAUGUACCUAAGAGGGGCGGUGCCAUUGUUUGGGGGCUUGGGGGGCUUUCAAAGGGGAAAAUGCGAUGGGAGAGGGAGGAACUGGAGGGGGGUGCUUUUGUACUGGGAUUUAAGACACCCCUGAUGGAAUGAAAGCCAACUGAACCACGUAAAGCUCGAACCACGUGGCAAGUGGUGGACAAAACUUCAACGCAUGAUAUUUAUUGGCACUUCCUCACCUCCCUUUGCCCUGCAGCUGUUUUUAUGCUUCUUUUUCUCUCCUUGCUAAUUACUGACUCCCCAAGUGGCAAGUUCCGCAGAUAGCUGGGUUAGAAGAGAGACAGGGGAGUGAGCUAGUCAAAUGUGAAAAAUGCUCUCCCAGCAAAGCUGAGACAAAAUUGGAGAAGCUGCAGCCUCACGCACCAUCCCCCUCUUUCCACCAGAUGGAUGUUGACUUGGUGUCUGGGAGUUCCCGAACCCUAGAGCCAGGAUGUUCUGUUUAAUCAACAGCUCAGCCAGCUGCCUGGGAGUUUUGGCAUUAAGCCCCGCCUUGAAGGGCGAGCUUUAAGUUUUUCCCAGUUCUGGAACUUUCUACCGAGUAUCCACCACCCUUAGACACAAUCCCAGUGCUACCCGUCUGACCUGCACUGCUCAUCUGCUUUGUGUAACAUGACCCCUGAUAAGAUGUUGAAACUGUUAUUCACAAAGACUCCGUGUUUGGGCAACAUCAAGACUGUAAGUGUAGAAUUGAGCAACUGUCUUCUAUCAAUAAAGGCUGAAUGGCA